ACAGAAGGAGGAAGGACAGCACAGCUGACAGCCGUGCUCAGACAGCUUCUGGAUCCCAGGCUCAUCUCCACAGAGGAGAACACACAGGCAGCAGAGACCAUGGGGCCCCUCCCAGCCCCUUCCUGCACACAGCGCAUCACCUGGAAGGGGCUCCUGCUCACAGCAUCACUUUUAAACUUCUGGAACCCGCCCACCACUGCCGAAGUCACGAUUGAAGCCCAGCCACCCAAAGUUUCUGAGGGGAAGGAUGUUCUUCUACUUGUCCACAAUUUGCCCCAGAAUCUUCCUGGCUACUUCUGGUACAAAGGGGAAAUGACGGACCUCUACCAUUACAUUAUAUCGUAUAUAGUUGAUGGUAAAAUAAUUAUAUAUGGGCCUGCAUACAGUGGAAGAGAAACAGUAUAUUCCAACGCAUCCCUGCUGAUCCAGAAUGUCACCCGGAAGGAUGCAGGAACCUACACCUUACACAUCAUAAAGCGAGGUGAUGAGACUAGAGAAGAAAUUCGACAUUUCACCUUCACCUUAUACUUGGAGACUCCCAAGCCCUACAUCUCCAGCAGCAACUUAAACCCCAGGGAGGCCAUGGAGGCUGUGCGCUUAAUCUGUGAUCCUGAGACUCUGGACGCAAGCUACCUAUGGUGGAUGAAUGGUCAGAGCCUCCCUGUGACUCACAGGUUGCAGCUGUCCAAAACCAACAGGACCCUCUAUCUAUUUGGUGUCACAAAGUAUAUUGCAGGACCCUAUGAAUGUGAAAUACGGAACCCAGUGAGUGCCAGUCGCAGUGACCCAGUCACCCUGAAUCUCCUCCCGAAGCUGCCCAUCCCCUACAUCACCAUCAACAACUUAAACCCCAGGGAGAAUAAGGAUGUCUUAGCCUUCACCUGUGAACCUAAGAGUGAGAACUACACCUACAUUUGGUGGCUAAACGGUCAGAGCCUCCCCGUCAGUCCCGGGGUAAAGCGACCCAUUGAAAACAGGAUACUCAUUCUACCCAGUGUCACGAGAAAUGAAACAGGACCCUAUCAAUGUGAAAUACGGGACCGAUAUGGUGGCCUCCGCAGUAACCCAGUCAUCCUAAAUGUCCUCUAUGGUCCAGACCUCCCCAGAAUUUACCCUUCAUUCACCUAUUACCGUUCAGGAGAAAACCUCGACUUGUCCUGCUUCACGGAAUCUAACCCACCGGCAGAGUAUUUUUGGACAAUUAAUGGGAAGUUUCAGCAAUCAGGACAAAAGCUCUUUAUCCCCCAAAUUACUAGAAAUCAUAGCGGGCUCUAUGCUUGCUCUGUUCAUAACUCAGCCACUGGCAAGGAAAUCUCCAAAUCCAUGACAGUCAAAGUCUCUGAGACAGCAUCUCCCCAGGUUACCUAUGCUGGUCCAAACACCUGGUCUCAAGAAAUCCUUCUGCUGUGACCUCCCAAAGUGCUAGGAUUAAAACAUGACCCACCAUGCUCAGAGUCCAUUUUCAUUUCUGAUUUGAGUAAUUUUAAACUUUUCUCUUUUUUUCUUAGUCAAUCUAGUUAAUGGUUGUCAAUUUUGUUGAUUUUAUUUUGAAGAAUCAACUUUUGGUUUCAUUAAUUUCCUCUAUUCUGUUUCCAUUCUCCAUUUUAUGUAUAUCCACUCUAAUCUUUAUUAUUUCCCUCAUUCACUGUGCUUGGGUUUAGUUUGUUCUUCUUUCAUAUCCUGAAGUAUUAAAGUAGGUUGUUGACCUGAGAUCUUUCUUCUUUUUUAAUGUAAGAGUUUACAGUUAUAAAUUUCUUGCACAAGACUCAACUUCUCUGAACCUCUGAUUCCUUACCUGAAAAUUGCAAUGAGAGUACUUUCUUCUUACCAUUGUUUUAAAGGUUUAAUGCAGUCAAUGAAACAAUAUGCCACACACAGCGGAACCAAUGUCAGCUGCUAUAUUACUACCAUCAUCAUUAGCCUUGAGGUCAAAUAGUCCUAGAAUCAAAUCUCAGAUCCACCUGUCACUAGCCAUAUGACACCAGGAAAGUUUUUACACCAUGCUAAGCUUCUGUCUUUUCAUCGGCAAAAUGGAAAUAAUGUCUAUGUGACAGGGUUAUUGUGUGGCUUAAAUGAGAUACAGGUAAAGUAUUGAGCACAGGGCCUGGCACAUAGGAAGUGCACCUCAACAGUACCUACCUUUUUCCAUAUAUAUGGAAAAAGAGGUAACACAUAAAACACUAGGACAUGGUUACUGACUACUUGUGGGAGAGAAAAAAAAAGCUAAGGGCAAAGAAUCAAGUCUGGUAUGUUAGUUUUUACCAACUGAGAUGCAUCCAAGAUGGGAUUAGACAUACAAGGUAAUUUAUCAGGGAAGACACCUGUGAGGGAAUGUGGAGCAGGCAUGAAGGUAGUAUGGGAGAACCCACAGAACACUAUGCAGAGCUGAUUCCUGUGAAAAAGAAAGAGAAAGAAGUUUUAGGUACCAAUGCAGUUCUAAGAGUAUUUGCAAGGCUGAUGGGGAAUCCUCCAACCAGCCACCCAUUAGAGUUAAAUAGAGCCUCAGAGAACUAGGCUUGCUUUCACACCCUUCCUGGGAGCCUGUAGGAAAGAAGCUUUCUGUGUAAAGGAGGUAGUGA